AUUACCAGGCACGCGCAGGAAACAUGGCGGCGGCGGGUGUUGUGAGCGGGAAGAUUAUAUAUGAACAAGAAGGAGUAUAUAUUCACUCAUCUUGUGGAAAGACCAAUGACCAAGACGGCUUGAUUUCAGGAAUAUUACGUGUUUUAGAAAAGGAUGCCGAAGUAAUAGUGGACUGGAGACCAUUGGAUGAUGCAUUAGAUUCCUCUAGUAUUCUCUAUGCUAGAAAGGACUCCAGUUCAGUUGUAGAAUGGACUCAGGCCCCAAAAGAAAGAGGUCAUCGAGGAUCAGAACAUCUGAACAGUUACGAAGCAGAAUGGGACAUGGUUAAUACAGUUUCAUUUAAAAGGAAACCACAUACCAAUGGAGAUGCUCCAAGUCAUAGAAAUGGGAAAAGCAAAUGGUCAUUCCUGUUCAGUUUGACAGACCUGAAAUCAAUCAAGCAAAACAAAGAGGGUAUGGGCUGGUCCUAUUUGGUAUUCUGUCUAAAGGAUGACGUCGUUCUCCCUGCUCUACACUUUCAUCAAGGAGAUAGCAAACUACUGAUUGAAUCUCUUGAAAAAUAUGUGGUAUUGUGUGAAUCUCCACAGGAUAAAAGAACACUUCUUGUGAAUUGUCAGAAUAAGAGUCUUUCACAGUCUUUUGAAAAUCUUCUUGAUGAGCCAGCAUAUGGUUUAAUACAAGCAGGACUGCUAGACAGAAGAAAGCUGUUGUGGGCCAUUCACCACUGGAAAAAAAUUAAAAAGGACCCUUAUACGGCAACUAUGAUAGGAUUUUCCAAAGUCACAAACUACAUUUUUGACAGUUUGAGAGGCAGCGAUCCCUCUACACAUCAACGACCACCUUCAGAAAUGGCAGAUUUUCUUAGUGAUGCUAUUCCAGGUCUAAAGAUAAAUCAACAAGAAGAACCAGGAUUUGAAGUCAUCACAAGAAUUGAUUUGGGGGAACGCCCUGUUGUUCAAAGGAGAGAACCGGUAUCACUGGAAGAAUGGACUAAGAACAUUGAUUCUGAAGGAAGAAUUUUAAAUGUAGAUAAUAUGAAGCAGAUGAUAUUUAGAGGGGGACUUAGUCAUGCAUUGAGAAAGCAAGCAUGGAAAUUUCUUCUGGGUUAUUUUCCCUGGGACAGUACCAAGGAGGAAAGAACCCAAUUACAAAAGCAAAAAACUGAUGAAUACUUCAGAAUGAAACUGCAGUGGAAAUCCAUCAGCCAGGAACAAGAGAAAAGAAAUUCGAGGUUAAGAGAUUAUAGAAGUCUUAUCGAAAAAGAUGUUAACAGAACAGAUCGAACAAACAAGUUUUAUGAAGGCCAAGAUAAUCCAGGGUUGAUUUUACUUCAUGACAUUUUGAUGACCUACUGUAUGUAUGAUUUUGAUUUAGAAAUUUGUUGUAAGAACUGAUGCCGGGGCUGGGUGCGGAGGCUCACGCCUGUAAUCCCAGCACUUCAGGAAGUCAAGGCAGGUGGAUCACCUGAGGACAGGAGUUCAAGACCAGCCUGGCCAACAUGGUGAAACCCCAUCUCUACUAAAAAUACGAAAGUUAGAUAGGCUGGGUGGCACACGCCUGUAAUUCCAGCUACUCAGGAGGCUGAGUUAGGAGAAUCGCUUGAACCUGGGAGGUGGAGGUUGCAGUGAAACGAGAUCACGCCGCAUUACACUCCAGCCUGGGUGACAGAGCGAGACUCUGUCUCAAGGAAAAAAAAGAACUGACGGUGGAAGUAGAAGUGUGAAAUUACCUGGGGGAGGGACGCUAAGGGGUAGAAAACUUAAGGAACCAUUAUUUUAAGGGGCAAGAGAACUUAAGAUAUUUAUUUAAAGAACCAACAGCUUGUCUAACCAUCAACCUUUAAAUAAGUAUAAAUACUAGAAAUGUUUGACUUAUCUGCUAUGUGAGUGGCUUCUAGCUAAAGGAUAGUGGAAAUAAUGUUUUCUAGAUUAGUAACGCUUGAGACAUCCUUUAGAGAAGGUGGUUGGAUACUUAGCACAUUAAAACUAAAUGAACCUUGAAUUAUGGGCACAUUUUCUUCACUGUUCAUAAAUAUGUAAAUUUCUCUUGGUUUCCCAUAUGUAAGUUAGGGGAAGAUAUAAUCUCUGUUUUGAUCUUGAGGUAUCAGCCUCUUUGGUGACAGUAAGUCAAAAGUUGCAGAGUUUUCUUUAAAAUUUAAAAUGUAGUCAGUCCUGUCUAUGAGAACCUAUAAUGAGCUUCAGAUUGAAUUGUUGCAAGAAUAUUAAUAGAGUGCUUUUCAGGUUACAGAGUGCUUUCAUACUUGAUUUGAUUUUUAAUUCUCGUAGCAGCCUUUUGAAAAAGUGGGGAAAUCUCACUUUAUGAGUAAGGUUAUUUUGAUUCAGAGUGUGACUUAUGGUCACACAAGUAAAUAAUUGGUCUGGGAGUAGAGACCCAGGUUUUUAUUGCAGGCUGGAAUUCUUACCUCUACACCUUCAGCGCUUCAAACUCUUGCCAUUUAUUUUAGUUUCUGUUACCACUGUAGGGAAUAGGACCAUUCUCCUUGGGAACAGAAGGCAUUGCUCCAUUCUCUCAGAUGGUAAUUUUGAGAUAGAAAUUCAUAUGUAUUCUGUAGCAGGAGUUCCUGAAUGCUUAAUUUUCUUAGGACAUUGUCCCAAACCAGCUAACUGGAUAACUUACCAUCUCCAUUUGUUUAUACUAAUGUCACAUUCUUUCUAUAUAGACAUUUCAGUUACCUGAAACAUAGUCAAGCUUCCUGUGGAUAACUGGCCUUAUAGAAGCCAAGAUACUUUUUAUAAAAGCAAUAGACAACAUUUCUUACUCUUUACUCAUAGCAGAGCAACCUGGACUGUAAAUUUACUCUGUCUUGUAGGUGAUUUCAUUAUAUGGAGUUUGGCUUCUUAACCCAUAGGUGAGGUAUAGGUGUAUUUGCAUUGAAUACAGUCUCAGUAGGGAGGAGUGAGACAAAAAUUAUCAAAAGCAGACAAAAGAAUUUAAGGAAGGGUGAUUUCGAGUUAGUGAAUGCGGAUACUACAGAAAGUUUCUGUGGGUGGUAUCAUUGCAGGGUAUGUAAUGGUGAUACUGAAUAAUCAAUGAAAGGUUAAAUUAGGAGAGUGUCUAAUGUUUUUUAAGAAUGAUUUCUGAUCCUCAAGAUUUUUGUUUUUUAAUUUGAUACUCUAAAGGAUAAGCUUCAGUAACCUGGAAAAUUGAACUAUAUGUUGUUUAAAUUUUUCUUUUUGGUGUAAGCAAGUGUACAGUAGGAUGAUAAGGUGUUCAUUUCUCGCCUGCCCCCCACUGCCUACACUGAAACAAAUUUGCUAUGGAAGUAAUUUUAGGGAAGUACUUUAGAAAUUGUACUGGUGCUGAUUAAGAUAUGCAUCAUUCAGUUGUACUGCAGACUCUGAGAUCACUAAAUGCCAAUUUAAAUAUAUUUAAUCUUUCUUUAAUUAAAAGGAAUUUGUACAUUAAUUCCACCCCCUACAACCCAUGACAUACCCCAAAGAACAUAAUGUAUAAAAUAAAAUAGCUUAGGGUUUUUAUGGUUUUAGGUCUAAUGUUUGUGUCUUUAAUCCAUCUUGAAUUAAUUUUUGUAUAAGGUGUAAGGAAGGGAUCCAGUUUCAGCUUUCUACAUAUGGCUAGCCAGUUUUCCCAGCACCAUUUAUUAAAUAGGGAAUCCUUUCCCCAUUGCUUGUUUUUCUCAGGUUUGUCAAAGAUCAGAUAGUUGUAGAUAUGCGACGUUAUUUCUGAGGGCUCUGUUCUGUUCCAUUGAUCUAUAUCUCUGUUUUGGUACCAGUACCAUGCUGUUUUGGUUACUGUAGCCUUGUAGUAUAGUUUGAAAUCAGGUAGUGUGAUGCCUCCAGCUUUGUUCUUUUGGCUUAGGAUUGACUUGGCAAUGCAGGCUCUUUUUUGGUUCCAUAUGAACUUUAAAGUAGUUUUUUCCAAUUCUGUGAAGAAAGUCAUUGGUAGCUUGAUGGGGAUGGCAUUGAAUCUAUAAAUUAACUUGGGCAGUAUGACCAUUUUCACGAUAUUGAUUCUUCCUACCCAUGAGCAUGGAAUGUUCUUCCAUUUGUUUAUAUCCUCUUUUAUUUCAUUGAGCAGUGGUUUGUAGUUCUCCUUGAAGAGGUCCUUCACAUCCCUUGUAAGUUGGAUUCCUAAGUAUUUUAUUCUCUUUGAAGCAAUUGUGAAUGGGAGUUCACUCAUGAUUUGGCUCUCUGUUUGUCUGUUAUUGGUGUAUAAGAAUGCUUACCAUUCAGGACAUAGGCAUGGGCAAGGACUUCAUGUCUAAAACACCAAAAGCAAUGGCAACAAAAGCCAAAACUGACAAAUGGGAUCUAAUUAAACUAAAGAGCUUCUGCACAGCAAAGGAAACUACCAUCAGAGUGAACAGGUAACCUACAAAAUGGGAGAAGGUUUUCACAACCUACUCAUCUGACAAAGGGCUGAUAUCCAGAAUCUACAAUGAAUUUGAACAAAUUUACAAGAAAAAACAAACAACCCCAUCAAAAAGUGGGCGAAGGACAUGAACAGACACUUCUCAAAAGAAGACAUUUAUGCAGCCAAAAAACACACGAAAAAAUGCUCACCAUCACUGGCCAUCAGAGAAAUGCAAAUCAAAACCACAGUGAGAUACCAUCUCACACCAGUUAGAAUGGCAAUCACUAAAAAGUCAGGAAACAACAGAUGCUGGAGAGGAUGUGGAGAAAUAGGAACACUUUUACACUGUUGGUGGGACUGUAAACUAGUUCAACCAUUGUGGAAGUCAGUGUGGCGAUUCCUCAGGCAUCUAGAACUAGAAAUACCAUUUGACCCAGCCAUCCCAUUACUGGGUAUAUACCCAAAGGACUAUAAAUCAUGCUGCCAUAAAGACACAUGCACACGUAUGUUUAUUGUGGCACUAUUCACAAUAGCAAAGACUUGGAACCAAUCCAAAUGUCCAAUAAUGAUAGACUGGAUUAAGAAAAUGUGGCACAUAUACACCAUGGAAUACUAUGCAGCCAUAAAAAAUGAUGAGUUCAUGUCCUUUGUAGGGACAUGGAUGAAACUGGAAAUCAUCAUUCUCAGUAAACUAUCGCAAGGACAAAAAACCAAACACCGCAUGUUCUCACUUAUAGGUGGGAAUUGAACAAUGAGAACACAUGGACACAGGAAGGGGAACAUCACACUCUGGGGACUGUUGUGGGGUGGGGGGAGGGGGGAGGGAUAGCAUUAGGAGAUAUACCUAAUGCUAAAUGAUGAAUUAAUGGGUGCAGCACACCAGCAUGGCACAUGUAUACAUAUGUAACUAACCUGCACAUUGUGCACAUGUACCCUAAAACUUAAAGUAUAAUUUAAAAAAACUGUAAAAAUAAAAAAAAUAAAAUAGAUUAAAGGCAA